UGGCUACAGGAAAGGGCCACCAGGCAGGGCUAUGUCCUUAGGUAGAAAAACACUGCCACUGCCAACUCACAGCCCUUCAGGGCGCAGGGAGAGAGCCAGGAAAUUUUUAAAAAAUCAUCCCCCAAUCUACUGUCAAUGUGUCCCUUUGGCUGAAAAAAAAAGUCACCCUCCAAUCUCCUGUCAAUGUGUACCCUUUGGAGCCUGAGUGAAAGACAGCCCAUUGACGAGGCACAGACAUGUCUCCUCCCAGGAUGCAAAGUGUCACUUCUUUGGACUAGUCUCUCACUAUCAUCAUAAAUGCCUUGAGAAUGGAAUGUGGUUGGGAAAAAAAGGGAUUGGGAGUACAUAGGUACUCCCAGCUAUAAGUACACAGGGGCACCAGUGGAGGUUUUCUGAGCAUGGAUCCAACCACCCCGGCCUGGGGAACAGAAAGUACAACAGUGAAUGGAAAUGACCAAGCCCUUCUUCUGCUUUGUGGCAAGGAGACCCUGAUCCCGGUCUUCCUGAUCCUUUUCAUUGCCCUGGUCGGGCUGGUAGGAAACGGGUUUGUGCUCUGGCUCCUGGGCUUCCGCAUGCGCAGGAACGCCUUCUCUGUCUACGUCCUCAGCCUGGCCGGGGCCGACUUCCUCUUCCUCUGCUUCCAGAUUAUAAAUUGCCUGGUGUACCUCAGUAACUUCUUCUGUUCCAUCUCCAUCAAUUUCCCUAGCUUCUUCACCACUGUGAUGACCUGUGCCUACCUUGCAGGCCUGAGCAUGCUGAGCACCGUCAGCACCGAGCGCUGCCUGUCCGUCCUGUGGCCCAUCUGGUAUCGCUGCCGCCGCCCCAGACACCUGUCAGCGGUCGUGUGUGUCCUGCUCUGGGCCCUGUCCCUACUGCUGAGCAUCUUGGAAGGGAAGUUCUGUGGCUUCUUAUUUAGUGAUGGUGACUCUGGUUGGUGUCAGACAUUUGAUUUCAUCACUGCAGCGUGGCUGAUUUUUUUAUUCAUGGUUCUCUGUGGGUCCAGUCUGGCCCUGCUGGUCAGGAUCCUCUGUGGCUCCAGGGGUCUGCCACUGACCAGGCUGUACCUGACCAUCCUGCUCACAGUGCUGGUGUUCCUCCUCUGCGGCCUGCCCUUUGGCAUUCAGUGGUUCCUAAUAUUAUGGAUCUGGAAGGAUUCUGAUGUCUUAUUUUGUCAUAUUCAUCCAGUUUCAGUUGUCCUGUCAUCUCUUAACAGCAGUGCCAACCCCAUCAUUUACUUCUUCGUGGGCUCUUUUAGGAAGCAGUGGCGGCUGCAGCAGCCGAUCCUCAAGCUGGCUCUCCAGAGGGCUCUGCAGGACAUUGCUGAGGUGGAUCACAGUGAAGGAUGCUUCCGUCAGGGCACCCCGGAGAUGUCGAGAAGCAGUCUGGUGUAGAGAUGGACAGCCUCUACUUCCAUCAGAUAUAUGUGGCUUUGAGAGGCAACUUUGCCCCUGUCUGUCUGAUUUGCUGAACUUUCUCAGUCCUGAUUUUAAAACAGUUAAGAGAGUCCUUGUGAGGAUUAAGUGAGACAGUGCCUAUGAAACAAACACUAAGUGCAGUGUCUCUGGAACUGCCUUACUCACAGGCUUCCACCACAGCCCUAUGAGAGCUUUGCCAACUCUGCGGUCCAUGACUGUUCCCACUUUUAAUGAAUCCUACCUUUCGCAGAAGGCUGAAAGCAGGGCAGAAAAGAUCUACAUUUCUUUGGACACUGCACUUGAUAGGGACUCAAAGAAUGUUAUAUUUUUAAUUAAUUUCUUUUUCUCUUCCGUACAAUUUCUGUCUCAACAAAAUUAGAAGAAUUAAAUUUAAAACUAGCUCCAAAAGAGCAGUCGUCUUUCAUUUUGGCAGACCUUAGAAUAUCCCCCUAGCUUAAUAAAUCUUUGUUGAAUGGCUUAAUGAAUGAAUAAACUGGUUAAUGUUUAAGUUAAACCUCUGAAAAGUCUCCAUUUACCAGAUUUGAGUCACUAAAUUUAUUGCUUUCACUACUUUUGAAUUUUGCAAACAUGAAAUUAAGUUUUAUAAUUAGAUAAAUCAAUGUCAACACAUAUUUAAAGUUUGAGGUACACUGUCUUCCUGUGGUUUCCUUUCACAUGCCAUCCCUUAAAAUCCCAGCUACACGCCUUCCCAUUCCUUCCCCUUUGCCUUUGUUCUAAUCUUCCCUCUCUGGGGGCUCUCUAAUUCGUCCUGGAAGUUUCCAGUGGUCUUAUAGACUCCAUGUUCUUGGAGGACAGGCUGUAUGUCAGAUUUACCUUUUAUUCCGAAGAACUCGGAGCAUUUAUUUUGUUAAUUAAAUUGCACAUAUUUUUAAAAGUUACGUGUUCCACAGAAUAAAAUACUAAUUGUAAA